AGUAGCGAUAGCAGCGGCCGUGGAGGUGGCGUUGGGGACUGUUUUCUCUCGGAGGCCGGAGCGGAGCCGCGUCUGACUGAGGCGGGCAGCAAGCGGCCCCCUCGCUCCCUCCCUCCCUCCUCCGCGCCCUCCCCGCCGCCACCAGCCGUCAAACGCCAACCGCCGCUCCUGGGGAGGAGCCGCGGCUCGCGGGGCCGGAGCCAGGCCUGCGUCCGGACAUCAGCCGGAGCCGGAGCGAGAGCCGGGGCCUCGGCGUCCCCGCCCUCUCCCCGCCUCGGCCAGCGUCCGCCGGGCCCCCGCGCGUCGCGCCAUGGACUCGGACGAGGGCUACAACUACGAGUUCGACGAGGACGAGGAGUGCAGUGAGGAGGACAGCGGCGCCGAGGAGGAGGAGGACGAAGACGACGACGAGCCGGACGAUGAUACCCUGGAUCUGGGCGAGGUGGAGCUGGUGGAGCCCGGGCUGGGCGUCGGCGGGGAGCGGGACGGACUGCUGUGCGGGGAGACGGGCGGUGGCGGCGGCAGCGCUCUGGGGCCCGGCGGUGGCGGCGGCGGCGGCGGCGGCGGUGGUGGUGGCGGGCCGGGGCAUGAGCAGGAGGAGGAUUACCGCUACGAGGUGCUCACGGCCGAGCAGAUUCUACAACACAUGGUGGAAUGUAUCCGGGAGGUCAACGAGGUCAUCCAGAAUCCAGCAACUAUCACAAGAAUACUCCUUAGCCACUUCAAUUGGGAUAAAGAGAAGCUAAUGGAAAGGUACUUUGAUGGAAACCUGGAGAAGCUCUUUGCUGAGUGUCAUGUAAUUAAUCCAAGUAAAAAGUCUCGAACACGCCAGAUGAAUACAAGGUCAUCAGCACAGGAUAUGCCUUGUCAGAUCUGCUACUUGAACUACCCUAACUCGUAUUUCACUGGCCUUGAAUGUGGACAUAAGUUUUGUAUGCAGUGCUGGAGUGAAUAUUUAACUACCAAAAUAAUGGAAGAAGGCAUGGGUCAGACUAUUUCGUGUCCUGCUCAUGGUUGUGAUAUCUUAGUGGAUGACAACACAGUUAUGCGCCUGAUCACAGAUUCAAAAGUUAAAUUAAAGUAUCAGCAUUUAAUAACAAAUAGCUUUGUAGAGUGCAAUCGACUGUUAAAGUGGUGUCCUGCCCCAGAUUGCCACCAUGUUGUUAAAGUCCAAUAUCCUGAUGCUAAACCUGUUCGCUGCAAAUGUGGGCGCCAAUUUUGCUUUAACUGUGGAGAAAAUUGGCAUGAUCCUGUUAAAUGUAAGUGGUUAAAGAAAUGGAUUAAAAAGUGUGAUGAUGACAGUGAAACCUCCAAUUGGAUUGCAGCCAACACAAAGGAAUGUCCCAAAUGCCAUGUCACAAUUGAGAAGGAUGGUGGUUGUAAUCACAUGGUCUGUCGUAACCAGAAUUGUAAAGCAGAGUUUUGCUGGGUGUGUCUUGGCCCAUGGGAACCACAUGGAUCUGCCUGGUACAACUGUAACCGCUAUAAUGAGGAUGAUGCAAAGGCAGCAAGAGAUGCACAGGAGCGAUCUAGGGCAGCCCUGCAGAGGUACCUGUUCUACUGUAAUCGCUAUAUGAACCACAUGCAGAGCCUGCGCUUUGAGCACAAACUAUAUGCUCAGGUGAAACAGAAAAUGGAGGAGAUGCAGCAGCACAACAUGUCCUGGAUUGAGGUGCAGUUCCUGAAGAAGGCAGUUGAUGUCCUCUGCCAGUGUCGUGCCACACUCAUGUACACUUAUGUCUUCGCUUUCUACCUCAAAAAGAAUAACCAGUCCAUUAUCUUUGAGAAUAACCAAGCAGAUCUAGAGAAUGCCACAGAGGUGCUCUCGGGCUACCUUGAACGAGAUAUUUCCCAAGAUUCUCUGCAGGAUAUAAAGCAGAAAGUACAAGACAAGUACAGAUACUGUGAGAGUCGACGAAGGGUUUUGUUACAGCAUGUGCAUGAAGGCUAUGAAAAAGAUCUGUGGGAGUACAUUGAGGACUGAGAAUGGCCCUGCAUAAAAUGAACUCUGAAAACUUUACCAUCUAGAGUGCUCAUGCAAUUAAAACAAAACAAACACAAACAAGGAGGCACUAAGCCUAUUCUGACACCACUGGUCUGUAGUACCAGAAUUGUUUUGUUAAUGGAAAGUUUAAGUAAAUUAUAUUGUAAUAAAAAGGUAGAUAAACCAUUGUACAACAGUAUUCUAGGCCACCAACAAAAGUGUGACAGACACACUAAAAGCCCUCCAACUUUAACUUGUAACGUAGCUUCAUUCUCAAAGCUGACUCCUUUUUUUUCUUUUUCCUUUUCCUGAGUGUAGUACAGUUAAAAUUUCAAACAGCUCCUUGACACUGCUUUUCAUGUUCAAACCAGCCAUUUUGUUGUACUUUGGUAAAGGACCUCUUCCCCUUCCUCCCCUACACAUACAGAUACACCCACACACAGACUGACUCUCUUUCUCUCAUACCCCAAGGUCAUGAGUGAAUGAUGCUUAGUUCCUUGUAAAGAAAAUCUUGGGAUGGGGAAAGGGGUAGGCAGCAAGAGGAUUCAACAAACGAAAAACAUAAAAACUUUGUAUAUGACUUUUAAAACAAGAGGACAACACAGUAUUUUUCAAAAUUGUAUAUAGCGCAUAUGCAUGGACAAAGCAAGCGUGGCACGUGUUUGCAUAAUGUUUAAUUACAAAAAAAUAUUUAUUCUUUAAAAAUCUUCAAGAUUAUGUCUAUUUGCUGUGCAUUUUCUUUCAGUUUGCUUAUCUUUCCCGGGUUGGGGUUGGGAUAAAGGUGUGUCGGUUUAGCACCUCUGGAAGACCUAUCUAGAGCUCUUUCACUUUCCUGAGGUUAUUUUGCCCUUUCUGGUGUUGGUAUGUCUGUUGCCGGCCAUGGGCCUCAUGCCUUGAAUUCCUGCUCUUGAUCAGGGACAAGGGAGGUCAAGCUCUGACUAAUGCCAUGACCUGAUUAAGGGGUACAGCAGGGAGUUUUGUUGCUACAGCUCAUGAAUUAACCUGUCCCAACCUAAUCCCCCUCCAUGGCAUCAUGCCUCUACCCAAGCCUUUGUGUGCCCAUGUUAUGCACACAGCUGUAGGCAUUCUUAAGUCCCCUGUCGCAUCCAGUGGAAGCAUUUUAAAAUUUCUUUUACUUUUUGGUUUUCCCUUAAUUGCUGCUUUUCAGAUUUUAGUUAUGGCUCGUCUGCUCACCCCUUCUCUACAUUAGGGUGUCAAAGAGAAUGUUUUGCUUUAAAUAUAAAUAGCCAUUCAUUUAGUCUCAGAUUGUGAAUUUAAAAUGGUGGAUACCGAAAUUGCUUGUGUGUGUUGCUGUGGGUUUGGUUUGAAGGCAAACACCCCUAGAACAUGAUAUUCCCAUCUAGUGCAUUUAAAUAGAAAUCACUGAGUUUGCUGCUUUUUUAUUGUCAGCAGAUAGGAGAAUUAAUAAUGCAUUUUAGCUGUGAUGUCCAUUUUUAUGAAAUUCCUACUAAGAGCUAUGUUAAAAGUAAAGGAUGGUGGUGGUUGUAUUAACUAUAUACCUGUUUAGGCCAUUCUGGCUGUGGUAUUUUUCAAUAGGUCAGCAUCUGUAAAUCUGUCAGUUUUAUACAGGAGUGCAGAGUGAACUAGGCAACUAGAUUAAGAGGUCUAAAUAUGAAAUACCAGUUGAGGCUGAGGACCUCUUCGUCUUCCUUUAAAUGUCUUUUGCCUAGGGAGUGUUUACCAUUUGUGAGGCAGCUUUGUCUGCUCUUACACUGUACAUCCUAUUACUCCAUUGGGAAGUAGGUUCACUUUCCUCUGGCCUUUUGCCUAAGUUAGGCUUUGCUGAAUCAACCCUACUUUUCCUUUUAGAAAAGGUUGUUACAGGAGAUUUACUGGCAACUGUUCUUUUCCCAUCAAAAAUCAGUGAAUGUUUGCUGAGUAUAAAUGCUGCUUCCUUAAACCACUUGUCGCUUUAGGAUCAACUUUACCUGUACCUUUUCUCCUUUCCUCCCUUGCCACCUCAGGUGCAAAUCUGAACUCAGUGUCUGCUUCUUCCAUUUUCUCGUCUCUCUCCCCUCUUCCCCCAUUAUCCAUAUGACAUUAUUUUACUUCAAAUGACAGCAUCAAUCUUAAAAAGAUAUACAUUAAAACUAAGGAGUUUUUUUAAAGAAAGCCUGAAUAAGUUCCUUUCCCUGGUAACUUUGAAAAGCAGUCAGAGUUGCUAUAUAGAUAUAUGUGGCUCCUUUAAAAUGCUUUGUGUAUGUGUGGUGUUUAAAAAAAAAAAAUCUUACCAGUUAACUUUGCAGUGUCUAGGUUUGAGUGUCAUAAAUCCACGUGUUCCUGUUGCAACAAAUACCCAAAAAUUGUGUGUGCACUUCCUAAUACCAGUCUUCACCCAUGGAGGAACAGUGCUUUUUAGAGAUGCUUUCUAUUUCAAUGUUGGCAUACUGCCUGAGGGUAUUGCAGUUGUGGGUGCAUUCCCUAAUUUGUAUGAUCAAGAUGAACUGGCCCUUUUCUACUUCCAAGCUUUUAACAGAUACCACCAUAUUUGACAGAAUUCCCAGAGUGAAUUGCUUGUGUUAUUAGUAGAUUCAGUGCCCCCAGCUGGGAUAGGCAAGCCAUGACAGCUUCCCUGUUUCACCUACAGAAGUCUUAUCUGAGGGAUCUAUUCACAGUAAGCACCAAGGUCUCCAUGUCUUGAGGUCAGUUUCAUUGUCUUUUGAAAAGUGCAUGCUUCAUUUGAACAAUUCAUUCAGCAGCAGAUGGACUUUCAGUGAUUUAAAAUAAAAUUUUGAUCCAAAGCUCAGGACACAAACCACAGUGGUAAAAUUGAGUAGCAUAUAAUAUCAGACUAAAUUAUCUGUAAUUUUCCACAACCCAGAUUGUAUGUGUUUUAUGUGUGUUUAAAUAAAUAUGUUAGAUACACGUGUAUACAUACACCCAUAUACAACAGAUCCAAGACUGGCUGACUUCAUUUGAAAUGGUUGAAUCUGCUGUGUAAUAAAGUGGUUCAACCAUGAUUAGGAACUGAAAUUUAGUAGAAGAGGGAAAAGGAGUUAAUGUAACAAAUUAUUUUAGCUACAAACCCCGGUAAUAGAGCACUUGGGGGAUGGGAUGGGGUGGGUUGGUGAGACAAUCAGAAUGGUAAAUUGAUUAAAUGCUCCUAACCCUGUAAUUUUGUGCAUAGAGCACCCUAUGCUGUGGAAAUAACUGUUCUUAGAUUUCAUUGUAACUGGACUGUUCAGGUUGCCCAGAGGGAAAGAACAUUCCUAAUUCUAAUAAAAUAAACUUUUAUUUUGUUAUUCCAUUAGUUACUUAUGUUUAUUUUUAUAGUUAAAAAAUGACUAAAGGUGGCUAAUAGCCACCCGUAUUAUGUGCCUUAUUCACUGUUCCCACUUAAUAUAAAAUGUCAAAAAUUGGUUGUUUCUUUGCAGGGAACUGUGAAUGAGCCCAUUCCCCCAACAUUUAACUUGGUUAAUGAAGCUUUCAGAGCAUUUUCUGAAAGAUUUCCAAUUUCUGCAUCUCAGAUAUUGAAUUUAAAUUGUUUGUGUUGUAACAGUGAUACAAAAAUGUUCAAUAGCUCUUUGAAUGCCACUUUUUUUAAAGAAAAUACUUUAAAAGUCAUUCUUAGCUAACCUCAAAACUCCUUUACAUUACUUUCAUUUUAGCUCACUCUUAAAGCUGAUACUGUUAUAUAGGGAUGAAGGGAGAGUUUUCUUAAAGAAGGUCCCAAAGUUGAAGAUCGUUUGUCAUUGAUACUCUGGCCAAGUCCAGGUUUUAGGACAAUUUAAUUUACUCUUAUUUGGAUCUGUAAUUAUGGGAGUUUAUCACUUUUCCUCUUCAAAGCACUUCAACUUACUGUCUAAAACAAGUGGAGAAGAAAUUGCCAUUUUUUAUAAAGGAGGAAGAUAAGGCUCACUGAGGUUAAAUAACUCCCUCAAUUUUUCAUUUCCUUCUACCUGAAACUUAACAUCAUGCUACCUCUUUGUAUCAUAUUUUGUUAUUCUGGUCACAGAAUGACCUAGUAUUCUGUACCAGGGAAGGUAGUUCUUAACUAUAUUGUACUUUUAAACCACAUUAAAGACUAUUAUAAAUGCCUAUCACUGCUACUGUUAGAGGUUGCUCUAUACUAUCUCUGAUCUUUCAUUUGUUGCAGUUUGCAACACAGUAGUUGAGAAUAAGUGGUUUAGUAUGAUUUGCUUAAUAGUACCCAAGUAAUUUGCAGUUGUUGGUUUAGUUAUUCAAAUGAAUUUCCAUUGUAAAGAAUUUUGGAUAGUCUGCAGGAAAUUGUUACAGGAUGCACAGAACAUCCCAUAUCCAUUGGAUCUCAGCCUUUGAGGCUUUAAAAAGAUGAUAAGCAGUGAGUUUUAUGAGAAAAUUUUGGCUCCUUCAGAAACAGGAAGAUAAGUGGGCCCCUCAGAUUUUUCAUAUAUCUUUGGGGAUAAAGUUGGUUAUAUCUGGUUUAUUUUAGGGAUUUUGCUUCUGUAGUUACCCAAGAUCAAAUAGCCAACUCAGAAAUACUCAGUUGGAUAUCAAUCAAAUAGUGCCUACCAGGGGAGUAAACAGACAACUUUUAGGUUUUUAGUUUUUGCUUUUGUGUGGAGUUGAGUCCAAUUUUUAAGGCAACUAUUGUUGACCUUUCUCUAGGCGGUAGCAUUUAGGAUGGGAAAAAAUAAUAUGAGUUAUGUGCGAAAAGCAGUUUUCAGGCUAUCAUUUAGGGCCACAGAUAUGCUUAUUUAGGACUAUUUUCAGGGUAGGAGCCAGUUAAAGUUUGUAUAUCAGUCACACAUUGAUAUGUAGCAGCUCUAUCAAUACCACAACAACCUUAUUACCAUAGUAAUUCAGGGGUCUCAAGUAAUCCAGGAGUCUCAAACUGAAAUGUCAACAAGAGCCAAGUAAAUAUUUUAGAAAUAGAGUACCCUGGAGUAGAUGGGCUCUGAGAGGAGCCUGUGAAAUCCAGACUUCAUGUGAAUUCUCUUAAUUAAAUGUGGGCCAAAGAAAACCCGGCCAUGGGCAGUUUUUUUUUCCCAGCUUCUACUAGUCUUGGCUUGCAACAAUGCCACUGUCCAUCUGGCAUUACCUAGACCAGUGAUACUUAAACUUGACUGCGAAUUGGAAUCACUGAGAAGCUUUAAAAAAUAUUAGUGCCUGAGUGUUACUUUAUGGAGAUUAUGAUUUAAUUGCUUUGGGUAGGCAUCAGUAAUUUUUGUAAAGCCCUUUACGCAUUCUCACCCCUAAUUCCAGCCGGUGAUUCUCACAUGCAGACUAGGUUGAGAUCCUUGAUCUAGACUGCCUUCUAUAGUUGCAAAAAGAGAAUAUAGGCGAGCAACUCCAGAUCAUAAGGGACAAAAUGAUUCAAGGCAAAUUGACUGGCUCAGAAUAGGGCCUCACUGGAGGCCCUAGUUGAGUGGGUUUUGUGGAAUGGUGCCUCCCAAGGGUCUGGUGUGCAGUGCCCAAUUUGGUUUUUUGUUGGUUUUCUGGUAAGUGGUCCACCUUGGAGAAAAUCACAAAACUAAAAGUCUUACCAAGAAGUAGAACUGACAAGCAGCCAUGUUGAUUGGCAGUACAUUCUCUUACCAAGGGGGAGAAAUCUAUCUAGGGAAAAUAAUACAGAGUCUGAGCAAAGGAAGUUGAGUGGUUAUAAGCAAAACUGUCAUUAAAGCUAGUUGCGUCAAGUCUGCACAAUUCCACGAGCACUUAAGAGUUUACAAGUUUCUCAUGUCUAUCAUUCUUUUGAUAAUCUUGUAUUUUUAUUUCAAGUGUGGUAUAGUAGUAAGAAUAUUGGUAUUUCUCAGCCAUAGAUUUCCCUUUUGUAAAAUGGGAAUACUAAUAGGAACUGUAAUUUGUUGAGUGCUUUUUGCCAGAUGCCUUACUUUUGUCUGUAUCUUCCAAGCAGCCCUAAAGCAAAAUGGGCAUUGUUACCCUAUUUUUAUGAGGAAAGACACUCAUAUACUACUAACUUACUCAAAAGUUACACAUUGAGUGUAUAACAGGGCCAUGCUUGUCUGAUUCCAUAUGUUCAUUCUAUUAUGCUGCUGUUGUCUGUUACAUAGGAAUAUUGUGAGGAUCAAAGAACAUGUGAAAACAAAACCUAGUUACAAUAAUAAGCACACCAGUGCUAACUUGGGCAAAAGAUAAGGAUACAGAGCUGUCUCAGAGACUCCCAAAGGCAGGAUGAGAUUGGGAACUAGAAAACCAUUUUGGACCCCUAAAGUGGUAUUGUCUACUAUCUGUACAUCAUUCUCUUACAGCUCUUACUGCUGCUUUUCCUGUCAGUUACCCCAUAGCUCCAGGUAUUACAUGUUAACUGUUCCUGACACAUGUAGACAGAACCAAUCAGAUCCAUGGGGCAGGAUCAUCAAUACAAACAUGGGUGUUGAGAGCUUAACUUAAUCGGGAAGGAGAUCUUGGAGAUCAUAGUUCGCUGGGUUCACAUCAUGGAAAUCGUCUUUGACAAAACUGAAAUGCCCUGAAGUUUUAAUUUUUUAAAUACAUGUAAUGAAUUGGUAUAUGGUAGAUACUCGUGGCUACUUAGUAUUUACCAAAUGCUUUGUUUCCAUCUCGUUUAUUUUUAUUUUUUAUUUUUUUAAGAGACAGUCUUGCUAUGUUGCCCAGGCUGGACUUGAACUCCUAGUCUCAGCCAACCCCUUCUGCCUCAGCCUCCUGAGUAGCUGGGAUCAUAGGCAUGUGCCACUGCUCCUAGCUCUUCCAUCUCAGUCUUAUGAUGUAGUUACUAUUUUCAUUUUAUAAAUAAGAAAAUAGAAGCUCAAAUAAAAUGGGUAGUUUCCUUGAGGUCAUCCUGUUAGUAAGUGGUGGAAUGAAGUUACAAACCUAGGUUUUAUUGGUCAGCACACACAGUGCCGGGCACUGGCAGUACAGCAGUGAACAAAAGGUCUGUUGGUUUGUCUGAAGCUCUCAACCUUGAUUCUGCAUAGACUCGGUGGAUUGCCCAAGGCCACUCAACCAGUUAAUAUCAGAGCCAGCUCUGCUGUUUGACCAGUAUAUUAUUUUCACCAUGCUGUAUCUGCUUCUCAGUCACCAAAAGCACCAGCUAAAAUUGUAUAUAGACUGAUUAGGGGACUUCCAACCUAAGAUUGUCCUGGAAACUUAAUUCUUAUCUUGGCUCAUCUCUUCAAAACAGAUGCCUCUUUCGUUGGUGACCUCAGAUACACUGUUCAGAAGUACUCAAAGUAUUCCUUUUUUCUCACAUUUGAGAGUCACUCUAGCAUUUUAAUGAGUUAAGCAAGCCAGCCCUGCAUUUCCAAACCCUUCCCAGAAGUCUAACCUUACUUUGAUCUGAUGACAUGGGCUUUUUAAAAGAUUACUAUUUUUUUAGAGGUGGGGUCUCACUAUGUUGCCCAGGCUGGAAUAUAAUGGCUAUUCACAGGCACAGUUAGGGUGCACUACUGCCGUGAACUCCAGGACUCAAGCCAUCUUCCUGCCACAGCCUCCUGAGUAACCUAGGACUAUAGGUGCAUGCCACCAUGCCCAGCUGACAAUGGCUUUAUAUACAUAAUAUUUCCUCAGCAACAAUUUAUGUCUUAUUUGGCACCUGUAAAACCCUCUUCACUGAUUAUGCCUGUUUAAAGGUUUGGUAUUUACUCCAAGUCACCUGCCUUUAGCCAUGGAGUAUUCAAGUUUCUUUCAGAAUGAGAAUUUGGAGGGUGCUCAUAGAAAUAUAAAACAAGGCUGGGCAUGGCGGCUUACACCUUGUAAUCCCAGCACUUUAGGAGGCUGAGGCAGGUGGAUCACGAGGUCGGGAGUUCGAGACCAGCCUGGCCAACACAGUGAAACCUCAUCUCUACUAAAAAUACAAAAAUUAGCCAGGCAUGGUGGUGCAUGCCUGUAAUUCCAGCUGCUCGGAAGGCUGAGGCAGGAGAAUCGCUUGAACGCGGGAGGUGGAGUUUGCAGUGAGCCAGGAUCACACCACUGCACUCCAGCCUGGGCGACAGAGAGACUCUGUCUCAAAAAAAAAAAAAAAAAAAAAAAAGAAGAAGAAGAAGAAAUACAAAACCAACUCUUUAUAGUAGACAGUUUAUCCCCCAGAAAGCUUUUUAGGCUGAAAACGUUUCUAUAGAUUUUGGAUUUCCUUCUGAUAGCUAAAAUUUGUUUCUGUAUAACAGAGUAGUGCCCUAUAAGCCAGUUCAGUGCACAUUAAAUGGCUGUUCUUAGAAUUAUGAAUCUGAGGCUUAUGCAGUGAGGCUCUAGCUCUCUGGAGUCAGUUGGUCAAGUGGGAUUCCUGAGGACUGAGCAAACACACACAGAGCAGGAUUUUGUCCUAAGUUUUCUUAGGGAUCCUAUCCAAAAACACCAUUACUUGAAUUUCCCAGCUUCCUUUUACAGGGAGACUUCCUUGCUAUGUGUACUCCCACCUCGGUAUGUCAAAUCAUUUUCUCAGAGGAAGUACAGCAUAAAAUAAUAACCAGCAUUUGUAGAGCACUUCUUGUGGGCCUUCUUGGGCAAAUAGACAUUCUCAUGGAAUGCUCUAAAAUUGUUAAGUUCUUGCACUUGCUCUCAAGUCAUUUAUAAUCUAAUUGCUGGUCUUCCUGGUAUGAACAAAGAUGUUUGCUUGUUAAUAAAUUCCUACCACAUACCCAGACUUGUGGUUUAUUUCUAUCUAACUAGGGAAAGCACUAAAGAGUUUUCCAAUAAGGAAGAAUGAUCUGAGUGUCUACCUGCUUUGGAAAAGAUGUCUGCCAUGGAUAGGAAAUGAUUUUGUAUCCCAAAAUCCUAGUACUAAUUUGGAGUGUUGUAAAGGUCAGGGCAGCAAAUGCUAGAGAGUGGGAUUAAUGAAAAGUUAUAGUGUUCUGCAUGCCUUUGAAUAAUUAAUUUUUACUCCAUUUUUACUCGCUUGCAAUAAAGUAGGUUAAGUGCUGUACUUUAAGGAAGUCCAUGUACAAGCCAGUGCCUUAACAAUGGUCAAAUGGUUGCUCACUAACCAAUGGAAAUAAAUGACUGUUGUUUCCACAAAAUUGCUUUACAGAUUCUAAAUGCUAUCUCUGGGACACUGGAUUGUGUGCUCUUUAAGAUAAAUUCCAUAAUCAAGGGCCUGGCCCUGAAUAGAUUGGAGCCCAAAAAUCUCACUGAAGCAAAGAGAUAAUAGGCCAGUAAAGAGUGGGAGACAAACACUCCUGGAAUAGGAAGCCACUACUCACCUUUAUUUUAAAUUGAUAUAUAGAAAUUAAUAUUACAAAAUGCACACAUCUUAAGUGUGAAGUUUGAUGUUUUGACAGUUGUAUACGUCUGUGUAAUAACUACCAAAAGAAGACAUAAUAUGUUACAAUUAACCCAGAAAAUUCUCAAGUACUUUUAAAUCACCCCUGAGCACCUCCCCACUCCAGUGAUCACUUCUUGAUUUUUAUCACUAAAGAUUUGUUGUACCUGCUUUUGGAUUACAUAUAAGUGGAAUCAUAUAAUAAUGUACUCUUUUGCAUCUGGCUUCUUUCACUGAUAAUGCUUUAAAGACACGCAUACUGUAUGUAUUAGGACAUUGUUCUUUAUUGCUGAGUAGUAUUUCAUUCUAUAAAUAUACCACAAUUUGUUUAUUCAUUCUCCUAUUGAAGGACCUUUAGGUUGUUUCCAGUUUGGGGCAAUUAUGAAUAAGGAUGCUAUCGAUAUUCUUACACAGCCUUUUGUUUUUGUUUUUUGUGGAUAUACAUCUUCACUUGUCUUGGAUAAAUAAGAGUAGAAAAUUACUGGGUCAUAUGGUAAGUGCAUGUUUAUAAGAAACUGCCCUCUUAUUCUCCAAAGUGGUUUUACCAUUUUGUACUCCUAUCAGUGAUGUAUGAGAGUUACAGUUGCUUCACAUGUCUGUCAACAUUUACACUGUCACUGUUUUUUAUAUUAGCCAUUUUAGCAUAUAUGAAAUAACUGAUUUUAAUUUACAUUACAUUUCCCUGAUUAAUGAGUUGAGCACUUUUUCAUAUGCUUAUUUUUCAUUUGUAUAUCUUUCAAGAAGUGUCUUUCAUGUCUUUUCUCAUUUUAAAGUUGGGUGUCUUUUUAUUGUAGGUGUUAUUCUUUGUAUUUUGAAUAUAAAUCCUUUGAUAGAUAUGCUAUGAUUUUUUAAAGACUCUAUGUAUUCACUUAUUGGGAUCUUUCGAUGAACAAAUUUUUUUUAUAAAAUCCACUUUAUCAGUUUUUUAUUUUAUGGUUUUAUGACCUCAAAGUCACAAAGAAUAUAUUUUCUUCUAGAAGUUUUAUGGUUUGGGAUUUUAUGUUUAGGUCUGUGAUCCAUCUCAAAUUAAUUUUUGUGAACAGAAUGAGGUUUGGUUUUUUUCCAACAUGGAUAUACAGUUGUUCCAGCAACAUUUACUUAAAAAGACUUUUCUUUACCCAUUAGAUUGACUUGGUAGCUUGGUUAAAAAUUGAUCACGUGUGUGUGUAUUUCUACAUUUUCUGUUCUGUUCCAUUAAUCUAUUUGUGUAUCCUUACAUCAGUACCACACUUUGGAUUAUUGAAACUUUCUAGUAAGUCUUUAAAUUAGUAAAUCCUUCCUUUUUGUUAUUUUUCAAGAUCGCUUUGGUUAUUGUCGAUUCUUUGGAUUGUCAUAAAAGUUUUACAAUUAGCUCAUCUUGUUUUUCAAACGUAGAUGUGCUGGGUUAGCUGUGUUCAUGCCACUGCAUUCCAGCUUGGGUGACAGCAAGACCCUGUCAAAAAAAAAAAAGAAAAGAAAAAACUGCUAGAAUCUUGAUAUGGGGUUUUGUUGAGUCUAUAGGUCAAUUUAGAAUGAACAUUUUAAUAGUAUUGAGUCAGCUAAUUCAUGAACAUAUUAAGUCUUGUCAUUUAUUUAGGUAUUAAAUUUUUUUCUCAGCAAUGUUUUGUAGCUUCCCUUGCGUAACACUUGCUUAUCUUACAUUAGACUUUUUCUUAAGCAUUUGAUUUUUAAAAUAUUUUUGAUUUUCUUUUCUUUUUCUUUUUUUCUUUUUUUUUUUUUGAGACGGAGUUUUGCUCUUGUUGGCUAGGCUGGAGUGCAGUGGCGCGAUCUUGGCUCACUGCAACCUCCGCCUCCCGGGUUCAAGCAAUUCUCCUGCCUCAGCCUUUUGAGUAGCUGGGAUUAUAGGCACACACCAUCAUGCCUGGCUAAUUUUUGUAUUUUUAGUACAGACGGGGUUUCACCAUGUUGGUCAGCCUGGUCUCGAGCUCCUGACCUCGUGAUCCAACCACCUUGGCCUCCCAAAGUGCUGCCAUUACAGGCGUGAGCCACCGCGCCUGGCUAAUUUUCAUUUUUAAGUUGUUUGCUGCUAGUAUCUAGAAAUACAAUUGAUUUUUUGUUUGUUUCUUUAGAGAUGGGUCUCACUAUGUUGCCCAGGUUGGUCUUAAACUCCUGAGCUCAAGGGAUUCUCAUGCCUCAGCCACCCAAGUAGCUGGGACUUUAUUCACGUGCCAGUGUGCCUGGCUGAUUUUUGUAUGCUGAUCUUGAAUCGUGCCACCUUGCUAAAUUCAUUUAUUCUAGAAAUAGUUCUUGUAGACUCCGUAGAGUUUUAUAUUAAAUAGAUACACAACAGUGUAGUCUGCAAAUAAUGUUUUUACUUCUUUUUCUGAUUUUAUGCCUUUUCUUCUUUUUUUUUUUUUUUUUUUUUUUUUUUGUCUUUCUCCACUGGCUACAAUAUCUAGUGCAAUGUUUAACGUGUGGUGAGAGCAGACACCUUGCCUUGUUUUCUUAAUCUUAGGGAUAAAGAUUUUAAUGUUUCAUCACUAAGUAUAAUGUUAACUGUAAGUUUUUCACAGACCAGCCCAAAGAAGUUCCUUUCUAUUCCUAAUUUGUUGAUAAUUUUUAUUAGGAAGGGUUAUUAAAUUUUGUGAGAUGCGUUUUUAGCUUUUAAUAAGAUUAUUAUGUAUUUCUCUUUUUAUUUUGUUAAGAUGGUAUGUUACAGGGGUUGGCAAACUGUGGCCCAUGGGCCAGAUCCAGCCCAUGGACAGUUUUGUUGUUGCUGUUUUAGAGACAGUCUCACUCUUUUGCUCAGGCUGCCAGGCUGGAGUGCAAUGACAUGAUCAUAGCUCACUGCAGCCUUGAGCUCCUGGACUCAAGCGACCCUCCUGCCUCAGCCUCCUGAGUAGCUAGGAAUACAGGUGCAUGUCACCACACCAGGCAAAUUUAAGAAAUUUUUUGUAGAUCUUGCCGUGUUGCCCAUGAUGGUCUCAAACUCCUGGCCUCAAGCAAUCCUCCUGCCUUGGCCUCCUACAGUGCUGGGAUUAGAGGUGUGAGCCACCACACUUGGCUCUCAUGGACUGUUUUUGUUUUUGUUUUGAGACAGGGUCUCUGUCACGCAGGCUGGAGUGUGGUGGCAUGAACGUGGCUCACUGCAGCCUCAACUUUCUUGGCUCCAGCAAUCAUCCUGCCUCAGCCUCCCGAGUAGCUGGGACCACAGGUGUGCGCUACCACAGCUGGCUAAUUUUUCUUUUUCAUUUUUGUAGACAUGGAGUCUUGAUAUGUUGCCCAGAUUGAUCUGGAACUGCUAGGCUCAAGUGAUCUUCCUGCCUUGCACUCCCGAAGUGUUGGCAUUACAGGCAUGAGACACAGUGCCCAGCCUAUUGCAGUGUUUUUUGUUUUUUCUGUUUUUUUUUUUUUUUUUUCAUCUUUGUUUUUGUUUUUUUGAGACUGAGUCUUGCUCUAUCUCCCAGGCUGUGGUGCAGUGGUGCAAUCUGCAACCUCCGCCUCCCAGGUUUAAGCGAUUCUCCUGCCUCAGCCUCCCAAGUAAGUGGGAUUAUAGGCACAUGUCACCAAGCUCAGCUAACUUUUAUAUUUUUAGUAGAAACGGGGUUUCACCAUAUUGGCCAGGCUGGUCUUGAACUCCUGGCCUCAGGUGAUCUGCCCACCUUGGCCUCCCAAAGUGCUGGGAUUACAGGUCACUAGGCGUAGUAGGGCUACUACGCCUGGCCCUACUGCAGUUUUUAAUAAGAGAUGAGUUCUCUCAGCUUUUGUCUAUAAGAGAAUGUCCUUACUUUUAUUUUUGAGGGGUAUUUUAGUUGGAUAUAGGACUCUAUGUUGACCUUUUAUUUCUUCUUUCAGUACUUUAAAGAAGUUAUUUUAUUGUACUCAGGCCUCAUUUGUUUCUGGUGAGAAGUCAUUCAUCAUUUUAAUUUUUAUUUCCUUUCCGUAAUGUGUGGUUGUUCUCAAUGGCUGCAUCUGUGCAUUAUAUUUACUUUUCAGUAGAUUGACUAGGGAAUGUCUAGGUAUGUUUUUCUUUGUAUAGAGUUUACUGAACUUCUUGGAUCUGUGUUGAUGUCUUUCAUUAAUAUUGGUUCUUUCUUGGCCGUUAUCCGUUUACAUUUUUCUCUUGUCUCAUACUCUCUUGCUUCUCCUCUUCUUUGGAGAUUCUAGUUACAUGUAUAUUAGAUGAUUUGAUAUAAACCUACAGAUCUCAGAUGAUUUUUCCCCUGCCCUGUUUUCUUUUUGUUUUCAGUUUGGAUACUUUCCAUUUAACCAUCUUUAAGUUUUUUGAUGCUUUCCAAUGUUAACCUGUUAAACUUGUUUAUUGAAUUCUCCAUUUAAAAAUUUUUAUUUUUAGUUAUUUAUGGAUACAUAGUUGUACUGAAUUAUUCAUUUCUAAUAUUUUUAUUUCUAGCAUUUCAUUAUAUUUGUAUAGUUACAAUUUUCUGCUGAAAUUUCCUAUUUCUUCAUGCAUGUUUUCCACAUUUUCCAUUCUACUUUUUAGCAUUUUAAUCAGUUAUUUUAUUGGGUUUUUUCUGUUUUUUCUUUCAUUUUUAAUCAGUUAUUUUAAGGAUCCAAACUGAUAAUUCAACAUCUGGGUCUUUUCUAGUUCUGCUUCUAUUGAGCCCUUCCUCUCCCUUACCAUGAAUCUUAUUUUCUUGCUUUUGCACGUCUUGUAUAUUUGAUUGGAUGAUGGACGUUUUAUGUUGAAAAAAAAAAGAAAUUGAAGAAAAUGUUUACUUCCAAAACAGAGCAUGCCCUUUGUUUUUUUUUCAGGCCACUUGAAUGGUGGCUCAAUCUGAUGUAUAUGAAUUCUAGACUGGGGCUUCACUGCAGUUUUAGUUUGAUUCAGUUUGCCUCUAGCUUCAAAUAUUUGAAGGAACGUAGAAUCAGAACUCUCAUAUCACCAGGGCCUGAGUUUUGGGCAUUGGCAAGAUUCCAGAGAUCUGACUUUGCUUCAUAGCUAAGCCACCAGCUUUUAUCAAUGUGGGAGAUCUUUCCCUACUUUACAACCUUGCUGCCAGGAUUUUUUUUUUUAAUCAAUGGGCUGGGGAUAGGAGGAUCUUUCUCAGCUCUCAUGUGUGCCCUGCCCUUUUGUAGAGGAAUGCCCACAAUGCCUAGGGGAUGGGUUUCUCAGCAUUUCUGACCCCAUUUAGGCUCCAAGAGUGCCUCUGUUGGAUUUCACAACAAUCCUGCCUCCCCUUUCAUUUUUAAAGGGUAUUUUGCCCUUGGGAGAAGUCAAGCUCUCUCAGCGUUCCUUCUAUUAUCCACACCUUUAGUGUACUACACCUUCCUGUACCUGGUUAUCAUCUAAGGGGUAAGAUUGGUGGGAAGCCUUCCUCUGUGGAUUUGGGUCAUCUAGGUUCUAAUGUCAAACCAGCCUCCAAGGGGUUGUGAAAAUGUUGUUAAAUUUCAGCAGGUUUCUCUUUUCUCCCCCCUGUAGUAUUCCUCUUCCUACCAUAGUUCAACUAGGAAUAACAACAGCUAGGGGGUCUCUUCUCUCCUAUGAAGGACUUGGCACUUUCUGGAGUUUGGAUCAUUUAGGUUUCUUUGGUUUUUGUUUUUAUUUUGAGACAGGGUCUCACUCUUACCCAGCCUGGAGUACAGCCUGUAGUGAUCUCAGCUCACUACAACCUCUGCCUUCCUGGCUCAGUUGAUCCUCCCACCUCAGCCUCCUGAGCAGCUGGGACUACAGGCGUGUACCACCACACCCGGCUAAUUUUUGUAUUUUUUGUUGAGAUAGGGUUUUACCAUGUUGCCCAGGCUGAUCUCAAACUUCUGAGCUCAAGCGAUCUGCCUGCCUCAGCACCCCAAAGUCCUGGGGUUACAGGCAUAAACCACUGCACCCAACCUAGAUUUCUUUGUGUCCUUAGCUUUCUGAUGAAUUAAACAUAUGUUUUAUUUUCUAGCUCAUCUGGCCUUUUGUUGUUGUUUGCUAGAGUGGGAGGUAUAUUCCUUGUGACUUUGUUCAUAUCACUAGUGAAUUUCAGAAGUAGGAGUUUAUUUUUUUAAUAAAAAAUUUUUUUAGGUCAGGCACAGUGUCUCAUGCCUGUAAUCCCAGCACUUUGGGAGGCCGAGGCAGGUGGAUCACCUGAGAUCAGGAGUUUGAGACCAGCCUGGCCAACAUAGUGAAACCCCAACUCUACUAAAAAUACUAAAAUUAGCCAGGUGUGGUGGUGGGCGCCUGUAAUCCCAGCUACUUGAGAGACUGAGUCAGGAGAUUUGCUUGAACCUGGGAGGCGGAGGUUGCAGUGAGCCGAGAUUGUGCCACUGCACUCCAGCCUGGGUGACAGAGCAAGACUCCCUCUCAAAAAAAAAAAAAAAAAUUUUUUUUUAAACACGUCUCACUGCCACCCAGGCUUGAGUGCCAUGACAUGAUCAUAGCUCACUGCUGGCUUGACCUUCUGGGCUCAAGUGAUCCUCUUGCCUCAGCCUCUUGAGUAGCUGGGACCACAGUCAUGUGCCACCAUGCCUGGCUUUUUUUUUUUUGUAGAGUUUGGGUCUCGCUAUGUUGCCUGUGAUCCUCCCACCUUGGUUUUCCAAAGUGCUGGGAUUAAAGGCAUGAGCCACCAUGCCUGGUUAGGAAUGGGAGUUUAAACAAUGGUUUUAUUUACAUAUUUCAUUAGCUAGUAUUUUUUUCUUUUUUGAGACAGAGUCUGGCUCUGUUGCCCAGGCUGGAGUGCAGUGGCACGAUCUAGGCUCAUUGCAACCUCUGCCUCGUGAUUCUCGUGACUCAGCCUCCUGAGUAGCUGGGAUUACAGGCGCCCGCCACCACACCCAGCUAAUUUUUGUAUUUUUAGUAGAGACAGGGUUUCACCAUGUUGGCCAGGUUGGUCUCCAACUCCUGACCUCAGUUGAUCCACCCGCCUCAGCCUCCCAAAGUGCUGGGAUUACAGGUGUGAGCCAUCGCUCCUGGCCUCAUUAACUGUUUUCAAAAGUAAAAGUACAUGGAUAAUACAAAGUUAAAUUUUGUAGAAUCAUAAAGAAAAGCAACACCUUCCCAUCUUAACUCCCCUAGUGCCUCUACUCCCUCCACAGAGACAAAUAUCUUACCAGUUGGUUGUGUUUUCUUUUCCAAACUGUAUUUCUAAAAUGUGUCAAUAUCUCUUCCUUUUAUUUUUUAUUUUUUGUAGAGACAGGGGUCUCACUGUGCUGCCUAGGCUGGUCUCAAACUCCUGGCCUCCUACCUCGACUUCUCAUAGUUCUGGCGUGAGCUACUGCACCUGGCCUCCCCCUUAUUAUUUUUUUAAACAUGAAUGGAAGCAUACUAUAUUUUCUACACUUUAUUUGUUUUAUGUAACUAUUUUAACAACCUGAGGACUUUUACAGGCUGCAUAAUAUGUCUUAAUAUGGAUGUAUCUUAGUUUAUUUAAACAGUUACUGGUGAUGGACAUUUCCAUGUUUCCAGUAUUUUUUCUCACAAACAAUGCAGUAUUAUGCCUUUGUCCACAUUCACCAUUGAUUGCUAUUGAGUAUAUCUGUAGCAUCAAGAAUAGGCAUACUGAAAAUCCUCCAUGAAGUCCAGUGAAGCUUCAUAUUAUUUUGAAGUGAUAUUUCCCAGUGUUGGCUGGACUCUCAAGCGUUUGUGGUAUAGGUUUUGGGAGGACUGGACACUUCCAAAGAGAAAUAAGAUGUUACAGACUUGUCCAGCAGGUGGCAUCAGAACAAAGCUGGCUAUGGACCUUGUCAGUACAAAUGAUAAAACAUUAAAAAUGUAAAAACUCAACUGUAGCUCCUUGUUUAUACAUAUAUUGGGGGUGUUGAAAAGUUACCGAUGCCUGAUUCCUCUUCUAUGUCCUCAGCCCCCACCAUAAAAAUAGAUAAAUGCCAUUUUUUUUGUAUGCCCAGCACAGCUAUAUGAUUUGAAUAAUCUUGAUAAGCAGGGUCACAUUUGAGGAGAUUUGCUAAGGGAAAUGAAGAUCCAUCUGUGACACAAGAAACAUGUUCUAUGUGAUUUCUGGGAUUUUCCUGUGAACAUACUUCUUGUUUGUUUGUUUUACAGUGGAUCUCACUCUGUCACCCAGGCUGGAGUUCAGUGGUGCAAUCAUAGCUCACUGCAACCUUGAGCUCCUGGGCUCAGGAGAGCCUCUCUCCUCAGUCUCCCAAGUAGCUAGGACUACAGACACAUGCCAUCAUGCCAGGCUCAUUUUAAAAUUUUUUGUAGAGACGGGUCUCACUAUGUUGCUCAGGCUGGUAUUGAACUCCUGGGCUCAAGCAAUCCUCCUGCCUCAGCAUCUCAAAGUGUUGGGAUUACAGGUGUGAACCAUAGUAUCCAACCUAUUAUGUUUUUUUAAAAAGAGAUUGUUCUAAUUAUGUAUAUAAUUAAAGUACAUUAGGUUUAGUGAUUGCAAUUUGAGAAACCAAUGUCCUUUCUUAUUGAAAAAGGCCCUGGUACAGAAAGUGUUCUAUCUUCCUCACAAGAUCUGAGGUCAAAGGAGAGAUUUUGAAACAUUAUAGCAAUGGCUUCUAGUUAUUGAAUAAAGAAUGUCAUUUGCUCCUCACAGGACCCCUUUCAGGGAGAUUUCACAUAUUGGGAAACAGCCUCAUGAGCUUUCUACAAACAUCUUUGUCCUUAAGUCUUCCCAUUUCAGUAAUUGGCUGUACCACUCAUCCAGCAGCUUUCAAAGUAAGAAACCUGGCAAUCUUCCUUUAACAUCCAUUUCCCUUUCCCUCAUUCCCCCAUAUCCAAUCAUGUGUAUUGGAGGUUUUUCCACCUCUAAACUUGAGAACCCAUUUACUUUUUCUCCAUCUCCUUUGCCAUCACACUAGUCCAAGUGAAGUGUUUCAUCAUCUCAUUUGCAGCAUCCUUUAGUUUACCCUAGAUUAUCAAUUUUUGUCCCCCUCCCAAUUCAGUCUCUACUCAUGAGCUAACAUGAGUUUAUUAAGUGUUCAUUCUGACCAUGCCAUUCCUUGCUCAAAAUUCUCUAGUGCCUUCCCAAUGCCCUUAAAAUAAAAUUCCUCAUAUGGCCUUUGUGGAUCUGCACUCCUACCUCUUCUCCUAUUGCAACCAACCCUGUUACCUUUUUCUCUUUUCACACUGGUCUUCAUUCUGUGCUGCAAACUGGCUGAGAUUCUUCCAUCCUCAGGGCCUUUGCACAAGUUCUUCCUUUGCCUUAGAAUUCUUUCCUGGCCUGCACAUGUCUUCAUCCCCUUUCCCUAAGCUAAUGCCUUACCCUUUAGGUCUCAUUUUAAACAUCUCUUACCCAGGAAAAAUUUCCCUGUCCAAACAAGUCUAGAUUGGCUCCCCAUUGUUUGUUCUAACUGUUCUAUAUUUCUCCUUCUUAGCAUUUAUCACAAUUCUUGGUAUGUUGUGCUUUUCACUUUCUUAGUCGCUAUUAUUGGAGUAGGUAAUACAUCCAUAUAGUACAAAAUUCAAAAUGUAUUAAAGGUAUAGAGUAAAAAGUCUUCUCUUCCCUGUCCCCCCGCUACCCAGUUCUCCUCUUUAGAACCACUUUUAGCAUUUUGAAUAUCCUUCCAGAAAUAUUUUCUAAGUAUACAAGCAAUUAUGUAUAUAAUAUUCCUCUUUAUUUUUGCCUUUUUAUUAAUACAGAUACUAUAUGCAUUUUCUGCACUUUAUCUGUUAAUAAUAUAUCUUGGCAAUUAUUCAAUAUUAAUAUGUAAAUAGUUGCCUCUUUCUUUUUCAUGCGCCAUAUAAUAUGGACUUAUAAUUUAUUUAACCUCUAUCUAGGUUGGUUUUAGGCAUUGGUUAUUACAAAUAAUGCUGCAUUGAAUACCUUUGUAUGUAAAGUCAUUUCCCACAUCUAUGCCUAUAGAAUAAAUUACUAGAAUUGAAAUAAUUCAGUUAAAGAUUAUGUGCAUUUUUAAUUUUGGUAGUUAUUGCCAAACUGCUCUCAAUGGAAGUUUUAUGAAUUCCCACUAGUGAAUGCAUUUGUCCUCACAAUUAUGUCAGUGAAAUUUUUGUUCUUUGCCAAUGCAAGAAAUGGAAAGUAUCUCUUGGAAACUAAUUUGCAUGUUUUUUUUCCUUGCACAGUUAUAUUUUCAUAUGUUAAAGAGCCAUUUGUAUUUCUUGGUGAAUUGUUCAUAAACUUUGCUUACUUAUUAUCUAAUGUCUGACUAAUUUGCUACACUCUAAAUUCCCAAUUCAUACUUAAGUCUCGCCCUUGCAAUUUAGAUGUACAAUCUGCCUCUUCAGUGGUUUCCACACCAAAAAAUCCACAGGCUCCUGAAUUUUAUAUGGGCCUAAGAGUCUUACUGAAAAUUGGAAGUCUUAAGGUGUAGUCUAUUUUAUGCAGUGUGAGGCCUUUCAUGCUCUGAAAUGUACCACUCUUGACUGACUUUUUCUUCUUCACCCUGUCCGGCACUGUGCCCUUAUUAGCCAGAGAAAUGUUCCCCCUUUCUCCCAGGAAACGUUCUGACCUUACCCUGGUCCCUCAAGGACUCUCCUUCUCCCCCAAAUUAACUUUCAAGGAGUUUCUCCAACCCAAAAUGGCACCCUUCCUGAAAAGAUUUCUAGUGGAUACUGUUUUCUGUACCUCACUACGGAUGUAUUUUGCUGCUUGGCUCCCCGUCUCCAUUUUGCUAUGGCAAACAUUUUUUUCCAGAAAUAUAUCAGAUAAAAUGAA